AUGGAAUGGGAAAACCACACCAUUCUGGUGGAAUUUUUUCUGAAGGGACUUUCUGGUCACCCAAGACUUGAGUUACUCUUUUUUGUGCUCAUCUUCAUAAUGUAUGUGGUCAUCCUUCUGGGGAAUGGUACUCUCAUUUUAAUCAGCAUCUUGGACCCUCACCUUCACACCCCUAUGUACUUCUUUCUGGGGAACCUCUCCUUCUUGGACAUCUGCUACACCACCACCUCUAUUCCCUCCACGCUAGUGAGCUUCCUUUCAGAAAGAAAGACCAUUUCCCUUUCUGGCUGUGCAGUGCAGAUGUUCCUCAGCUUGGCCAUGGGGACAACAGAGUGUGUGCUUCUGGGCGUGAUGGCCUUUGACCGCUAUGUGGCUAUCUGCAACCCUCUGAGAUAUCCCAUCAUCAUGAGUAAGGAUGCCUAUGUACCCAUGGCAGCUGGGUCCUGGAUCAUAGGAGCUGUCAAUUCUGCAGUACAAACAGUGUUUGUGGUACAAUUGCCUUUCUGCAGGAAUAACAUCAUCAAUCAUUUCACCUGUGAAAUUCUAGCUGUCAUGAAACUGGCCUGUGCUGACAUCUCAGGCAAUGAGUUCAUCCUGCUUGUGACCACAACAUUGUUCCUAUUGACACCUUUGUUAUUAAUUAUUGUCUCUUACACGUUAAUCAUUUUGAGCAUCUUCAAAAUUAGCUCUUCGGAGGGGAGAAGCAAACCUUCCUCUACCUGCUCAGCUCGUCUGACUGUGGUGAUAACAUUCUGUGGGACCAUCUUCCUCAUGUACAUGAAGCCCAAGUCUCAAGAGACACUUAAUUCAGAUGACUUGGAUGCCACUGACAAACUUAUAUUCAUAUUCUACAGGGUGAUGACUCCCAUGAUGAAUCCUUUAAUCUACAGUCUUAGAAACAAGGAUGUGAAGGAGGCAGUAAAACACCUACUGAGAAGAAAAAAUUUUAACAAGUAA